GACUUCCGGCCUCGGAGGCCGGCGUCGGCUGUUGCAGCCUGCUGCGCGCCCAGGGGUCCCGCGGGUUUUCGGGCGCAGGGUGGCGCCCGCGGCAGGCGGCGGCCAUGAACUUCUCCGAGGUAUUCAAGCUCUCCAGCUUACUCUGCAAGUUCUCCCCGGACGGCAAGUACCUGGCUUCCUGUGUCCAGUACCGGUUAGUGGUCCGGGAUGUGAACACCCUUCAGAUCCUUCAGCUGUACACGUGCCUAGACCAGAUCCAGCACAUCGAGUGGUCGGCAGACUCGCUCUUCAUCCUGUGCGCCAUGUACAAGCGAGGGCUGGUGCAGGUCUGGUCUUUAGAGCAGCCCGAAUGGCACUGCAAAAUAGACGAGGGCUCAGCCGGGCUGGUGGCCUCGUGCUGGAGCCCGGACGGGCGCCACAUUCUCAACACCACGGAAUUCCAUCUGCGGAUAACCGUCUGGUCCUUGUGCACAAAAUCCGUGUCUUACAUCAAAUACCCGAAAGCUUGUCUGCAGGGAAUCACCUUCACCAGGGACGGCCGCUACAUGGCGCUGGCAGAACGGCGCGACUGCAAAGAUUACGUGAGCAUCUUCGUCUGCAGUGAUUGGCAGCUCCUGCGGCAUUUUGAUACGGACACCCAGGAUCUCACAGGGAUUGAGUGGGCCCCAAACGGCUGUGUGCUGGCAGUGUGGGACACCUGCUUGGAGUACAAGAUUCUGCUGUACUCAUUGGAUGGCCGGUUGUUGUCCACGUACAGCGCUUACGAGUGGUCCCUGGGCAUCAAGUCUGUGGCCUGGAGCCCCAGCAGUCAGUUCCUGGCAGUUGGGAGCUAUGAUGGAAAGGUGCGCAUCCUUAAUCACGUGACUUGGAAAAUGAUCACGGAGUUUGGGCAUCCUGCAGCCAUUAAUGAUCCCAAGAUAGUGGUGUAUAAGGAGGCCGAGAAGAGCCCACAGCUGGGACUGGGCUGCCUCUCCUUCCCGCCGCCCCGGGCCGGGGCCGGCCCUCUCCCGAGCUCAGAGAGUAAAUGUGUAGAAGCGACUGGAAAAGAAAAUGAAGUUGGGGGUUUCCGACACGUCACCUCCUUUCACGUUUCUGCAGUAGCCGAGGUGCUCACAGAAGCUCCUUGGAGGCGCUGGGCCUUUGUCCUGCAGCAGCCGCAGACAACAUUCCCAAUGCCGUCUGGGUCUGGGACAUUCAGAAGCUGAGGCUGUUCGCGGUGCUCGAGCAGCUGUCCCCAGUGCGCGCAUUUCAGUGGGACCCGCAGCAGCCGCGGCUGGCCAUCUGCACGGGAGGCAGCAGGCUCUACCUGUGGUCCCCAGCGGGCUGCAUGUCGGUGCAGGUGCCUGGGGAAGGUAAGCACAUCCCCGAGGCCACGGACGUGGCAGCCUUGCUGUGUGCAGUCUGGCAUCACACGGGCUGAACUGUUGAAGCCCAGCUGCUGUCUCCGGCAGCACUCCAGGGAAACUGCCCUCAGAGUCUUUGCGUAAACCUCAAGACGGACACACAGGGGACCCGCUGCCCUCAGCUUUAUGGGCUAGAAGCAGCCUCUCCCUGACUUGAGGCAGCUCUGGGGCUCCACCCUGGCUCUGCCUAUGUGGGUCACUCCAGGCACUGUGCUGGCCUGCAGGACAAGGGGGUGCCCAUCCCCCAGAAUCUGGGCCUCCCCUGCUGUAAUCCUCUGGCCACCUGUCUCUCUCUAGGCGACUUUGCAGUGCUCUCUCUGUGCUGGCAUUUAAGCGGAGACUCGAUGGCCCUCCUCAGCAAGGAUCACUUCUGCCUCUGCUUCCUGGAGACAGAGGCAGUGGUCGGCACAGCCUGCAGACAGCUGGGCGGCCACACGUAGCAGCGGUGCACUAACGUGUGCAGAAACAGGGCUACUCUGUGUUUCCAGUGUGGGAAAAAACACAGCUUCACCAGGAGGUUCUCCACUGUGGUGGUCUGGAUUCAGUGAUUGAUUCUAUUUUUCUAUAGCAAAGCAUUUUUGUAAAUAUGUAUGGUAUAAAACUGUAGUUUUAUUAUUUAAAAUAAAUACUUGCUGAUUUAUACAA